AGAGUCGCGUUAUGGCCGAGGUGCGGGUGCAGCUGCUCCUGUCCCGGCGUCCGGAGUCGGUGAGCUUCGCACGGAGUGUGUGUGGCCUCCUGGGAGCCGGACCAGGGCUCGGGACGUGGCCCAUUCACUGCAGCUUGAAGCGAGGACGGCUUGUCCUCUCGAGCAGGCCCUUCCCAGGCGCCUCCGCUAGGCUUCCGCUCCAGCGACCCCCUUUCUGCCCUUUUGCGGCCCUGGAGGAGCGGCCCAGGGUCCCUGGGGCUGAGCUGCCCACAGAUCGAGGUGUGGACCUGGGUGUGGCCGUCAUUCUGCAGUCCAGCGACAAGACUGUCUUGCUAACCCGAAGGGCACGCACCCUGAGCGUUUCCCCCAACCUCUGGGUACCCCCGGGUGGGCACGUGGAACUUGAGGAGGAGCUGCUGGACGGAGGGCUUCGAGAACUUUGGGAGGAGAGUGGACUACACCUGCCCCAGGGCCAGUUCUCUUGGGUCCCUCUGGGUUUAUGGGAGUCUGCCUACCCUCCUAGGCUGAGCUGGGGUUUACCCAAAUACCAUCACAUUGUUCUGUAUCUACUCGUGAUCUCCCAGGAAUCACAGCAGCAGUUGCAGGCCCGGAUCCAACCAAACCCAAAUGAGGUGAGCGCCCUUAUGUGGCUGACACCAGAUGUAGCUGCUGCAGUGGCUGCCGCAGAGGAUGGGACAGAGACACCCGGACUUCUCCCCCAGGACCUACCACCCUCUGUCCUUGCAGUGGAACUAGAGGAGGAUGGAAGAGCCCGACCUCUGGUCCUGCACAUGUCCACCCUCCUGCGGAUGAUCCCAACCAUGGCAGAGGACAAAGAGAGAGUCAGCACUGGAACCAAGUUUGCCCUCAAGCUCUGGCUGCAACAUCUGGGCAGAACACCCCCACCGUGUAAAAGUGCAGCUUACCUGGACCCAGGGCCAGCAAAGGAAGAAUGGAACAUGGACCCUCUUCCCCCAAACCAGGGGUCUGGAAAGUGAAGUGUAAAAUCCCCUCCCUAGCCCAUCUCCAUGACACUCACAGAACAUUCACAACCUUUAUUAUGGGUGAGAGCUUCACUACAACUUUAGAAAUAAAAAGUAAAAUUACAACAUAGGUCCUAGGCCUUGGCGAGCCUGAAAAAGAAGAUUGGGAAGGAGGGCACAGGGUCCUUCCACCUCCCUGGAAAGGUGCAGAAUGAGCCAGGCCUAACUACAGGGCCAUGAGCCUCUAGAAGCUUAGGGGGGAAUAAGAAACACUGUGAACUUAGAUAUAUAAAUAGAGAGAGACCCAAGCAAUAGGCCGGGCCUGACUCCCAGACCCCUGCAGAUCAUGGCUAAGGCCUUACAUCCUCCUCUGUCAUACUGGAGUAGGAGGCAGGGGAAGUCAUCUUUGGAGUAUUUUGGUUUUUCUUAUUUAUGUACAAAAAAGUCCACAUCCACAAUCCAAAAUAAAGUUCUCUGUCCAUCUCUGAAA